ACCAGGAGGGUAUGCAUAGGGAGGGCAAGAGCUCUGGGCCACUGCGAAGAUUCAAAAGCUCCAAAAACCUACUGUAGACAUCGAAGAACCAAUAUAUACAAUGGGCCAACAAUCCAGUGUCCGCAGGCUGAAGAGGAGCGUCCCCUGUGAAUCCAACGAGGCCAACGAGGCCAAUGAGGCCAACAAGACGAUGCCGGAGACCCCAACUGGGGACUCAGACCCGCAACCUGCUCCUAAAAAAAUGAAAACAUCUGAGUCCUCGACCAUACUAGUGGUUCGCUACAGGAGGAACGUGAAAAGAACAUCUCCAGAGGAACUGCUGAAUGACCACGCCCGAGAGAACAGAAUCAACCCCGACCAAAUGGAGGAGGAGGAAUUCAUAGAAAUAACGACUGAAAGACCUAAAAAGUAGCAAGAAGCUACAUCCCUCAAACUUCGGCAAUGAAAAUAAAGUUUGAGAAGCUGA